GUACUCAAGAUGGCGGCUCCGGGCGGGCGUGGCCAGUGACUAGAAGGCGAGGCGCCGCGGGACCAUGGCGGCGGCGGCGGACGAGCGGAGUCCAGAGGACGGAGAAGACGAGGAAGAGGAGGAGCAGUUGGUUCUGGUGGAAUUAUCAGGAAUUAUUGAUUCAGACUUCCUCUCAAAAUGUGAAAAUAAAUGCAAGGUUUUGGGCAUUGACACUGAGAGGCCCAUUCUGCAAGUGGACAGCUGUGUCUUUGCUGGGGAGUAUGAAGACACUCUAGGGACCUGUGUUAUAUUUGAAGAAAAUGUUGAACAUGCUGAUACAGAAGGCAAUAAUAAAACAGUGCUAAAAUAUAAAUGCCAUACAAUGAAGAAGCUCAGCAUGACAAGAACUCUCCUGACAGAGAAGAAGGAAGGAGAAGAAAACAUAGGUGGGGUGGAAUGGCUGCAAAUAAAGGAUAAUGAUUUCUCCUAUCGACCCAACAUGAUUUGUAACUUUCUACAUGAAAAUGAAGACGAAGAAGUGGUAGCUUCAGCCCCAGAUAAAUCUUUGGAAUUGGAAGAGGAAGAGAUUCAAAUGAACGACAGUUCAAACCUGAGUUGUGAACAGGAGAAACCAAUGCACUUGGAAAUAGAAGAUUCUGGUCCUCUUAUUGAUAUACCUUCUGAGACAGAAGGUUCUGUUUUUAUGGAAACUCAAAUGCUGCCUUAGAAAUCACUCCUAGAUGAAAUGUUUCUCAUAAUAACUUGUCAAGAACUUUUUAGAGUUGUUACAUAAAAAUAAUUGCUGUGUA